AGCGGUUCCACUUCCUGUCUCCUGGGGUUGACGACCUAGCUGGGUAAGGUCUUCACGUCCUAGGAAGAAAUCGGUGGCUGCGGGAGGUCUUCGUGGACUGGGACUCGAACCUGACCGACCCGGCAGUGCGGGUGGGCGAGAGCGAGGCGCUCAGAGGAGGAACCCGGGGCGCAGACGGAAUCUGCCAGAUCCUUAGGCUGAGGGAAGUUGUGGCCAUGGAGGGUGCUUUCAAACUUAGUCUGCGCUCCAAGAAAAGCCUGGAGUCUCACGCUUGCCGUAUCCUUCUCCAGUCGUAUUAUUAUCCAAAAGAAGGACCGAGAGGAGGAUGAGAGCGUUAUUGUUGCACACUUAAGUCAAGGGGGAGAAGCCCGAGGAAGAUUGACCAAUUUUGUAAUUCUAGAAACAUGGUCCAUGGAUCAGUGACAUUCAGGGAUGUGGCCAUUGACUUCUCUCAGGAGGAGUGGGAGUGCCUGCAGCCUGAUCAGAGGACCUUGUACAGGGAUGUGAUGUUGGAGAACUACAGCCACCUGAUAUCACUGGCAGGAAGUUCCAUUUCUAAGCCAGAUGUGAUUACAUUACUAGAGCAAGAGAAAGAGCCCUGGAUUGUUGUAAGUAAAGAAACAAGCAGAUGGUAUCCAGAUUUGGAGUCAAAAUAUGGACCUGAGAAAAUAUCUCCAGAAAAUGAUAUUUUUGAAAUAAAUUUACCCAAACAUGUUAUAAAGCAAAUAAGUAAAACACUUGGCCUCGAGGCCUUUUAUUUUAGAAAUGACUCAGAAUAUAGAAGUAGAUUUGAGGGACGACAGGGACAUCAAGAAGGAUAUAUCAACCAGAAGAUCAUCAGCUAUGAAGAAAUGCCUGCUUAUACUCAUGCUUCUCCUAUUCAUAAUACACAUAAACCAUAUGAAUGUAAGGAAUGUGGGAAAUACUUUAGUUGUGGUUCAAAUCUUAUUCAGCAUCAGAGUAUUCAUACUGGAGAGAAACCCUAUAAAUGCAAAGAAUGUGGGAAAGCCUUUCAACUUCACAUACAACUUACUCGACAUCAGAAAUUUCAUACUGGUGAGAAAACUUUUGAAUGUAAGGAAUGUGGAAAAGCCUUUAAUCUUCCCACCCAGCUUAAUCGCCAUAAGAACAUUCACACAGUUAAGAAACUGUUUGAAUGUAAGGAAUGUGGGAAGUCUUUUAAUCGUAGCUCAAACCUUACUCAGCAUCAAAGUAUUCAUGCUGGUGUAAAACCAUAUCAAUGUAAGGAGUGUGGGAAAGCCUUUAAUCGUGGUUCAAAUCUUAUUCAGCAUCAAAAAAUUCAUUCCAAUGAGAAACCCUUUGUAUGUAGGGAAUGUGAGAUGGCCUUUCGAUAUCAUUACCAACUCAUUGAACAUUGCCGAAUUCAUACUGGCGAGAAACCCUUUGAAUGUAAAGAAUGCAGAAAGGCCUUUACUCUUCUGACAAAGCUUGUUCGACAUCAGAAGAUUCAUAUGGGUGAGAAGCCCUUUGAAUGCAGGGAAUGCGGGAAGGCCUUUAGUCUCCUCAAUCAGCUUAAUCGCCAUAAGAAUAUUCACACAGGUGAAAAACCAUUUGAAUGUAAAGAAUGUGGGAAGUCCUUUAAUCGUAGUUCAAACCUUAUUCAACACCAGAGUAUUCAUGCUGAUGUAAAACCAUAUGAAUGUAAGGAGUGUGGGAAAGGCUUUAAUCGUGGUGCAAAUCUUAUUCAGCAUCAAAAAAUUCAUUCCAAUGAGAAACCCUUUGUAUGUAGGGAAUGUGAGAUGGCCUUUCGAUAUCAUUACCAACUUAUUCAACAUUGCCAAAUUCAUACUGGUGGGAAACCCUUUGAAUGUAAAGAAUGUGGAAAGGCCUUUAGUCUUCUGACACAGCUUGCUCGACAUAAGAACAUUCAUACUGGUGAGAAACCAUUUGAAUGUAAAGACUGUGGGAAGGCCUUCAAUCGUGGCUCGAACCUUGUUCAACAUCAGAGUAUUCACACUGGUGAGAAGCCCUAUGAAUGUAAGGAGUGUGGGAAGGCUUUUAGACUUCACCUACAACUUUCUCAACAUGAGAAAACUCAUACAGGUGAGAAACCCUUUGAAUGUAAGGAAUGUGGGAAAUUCUUUCGUCGUGGUUCAAAUCUUAAUCAACAUCGAAGUAUUCAUACCGGAAAGAAACCCUUUGAAUGUAAGGAAUGUGGGAAAGCCUUUCGACUUCAUAUGCACCUUAUUCGACAUCAGAAAUUUCAUACUGGUGAGAAGCCCUUUGAAUGUAAGGAAUGUGGCAAGGCCUUCAGUCUUCACACCCAGCUUAAUCACCAUAAGAACAUUCACACAGGUGAGAAGCCAUUUAAAUGUAAAGAAUGUGGGAAGUCCUUUAAUCGUGUCUCAAACCUUGUUCAACAUCAGAGUAUUCAUGCUGGUGUAAAACCAUAUGAAUGUAAGGAGUGUGGGAAAGGCUUUAGUCGUGUUUCAAACCUUAUUCAGCAUCAGAAAACUCAUUCCAGUGCGAAACCCUUUGUAUGUAAGGAGUGUAGGAAGACCUUUAGAUAUCAUUACCAGCUUACUGAACAUUACCGAAUUCAUACUGGUGAGAAACCCUUUGAAUGUAAAGAAUGCGGAAAGGCCUUUGGUCUUCUGACACAGCUUGCUCAACAUCAGAUCAUUCAUACUGGUGAGAAGCCAUUUAAAUGUAAGGAGUGUGGGAAGGCCUUUAAUCGUGGCUCAAACCUUGUUCAACCUCAGAGUAUUCAUACUGGUGAGAAACCCUAUGAAUGUAAGGAGUGUGGGAAGGCUUUUAGACUUCACCUACAACUUUCUCUGCAUCAAAAACUUGUACAGGUGAGAAACCCUUUGAAUGUAAGAAAUGUGGGACAGCCUUCAGACAUCAGUAGCAACUUACUGAACAUCAGAAAAUUCAUACUUGGGUGAAAACCUUUGAAUGUAAGGAAUGUGGGAAGGCCUUUCAAUAUCAUUACCAAUUUCAUGGACAUUAUAGAUUUCAUAUUCGUGAGAACCCUUAUGAAUGUCAAGGAUGUGGGAAAUGCUUUACCAGUGGUAGAAACCUUAGAGUACAUCAGAGAAUUCAUACUGGUGAGAAACCAUAUCAAUGUGAAGAAUGUGGGAAAGCCUUUAGUCAUAGUUCAAACCUGUUAAACAUGUUAAAAUUCAUACUGAUGAGAAACCCUAUGAAUGUAAGGAAUGUGAAAAGGCCUUUAGCAGUAAUUAUGAUCUUACUGUACAUCUGAGAAUCCGUACUGCUGAGAAACCCUGUGAGUGUAAAGAAUGUGGAAAACUUUUGGAUUUAGCUUAGUCUUUACUGCACAUCAAAGAAUUCAUACUGGUAUGAACCGUAUGAAUGUAAAGAAUGUGGAAAGACCUUUACUUGUAGCUCGAGCCUUGUUCAACAUGUUAAAAUUCAUACUGGUGAGCAACCCUGUGAAUGUAAAGGAUGUGGGAAGACCUUUAGACUUAGUUCAGUCCUUUCUGCACAUCACAGAAUUCAUACUGGCAUGAAACCCUAUGAAUGUAAAGAAUGUGAGCAAACCCUUACUGUGAAUGAUCUGCUUACGCAACAUCAGAAAAUUCAUUAUAGUUAGAAGUUUUAUGAAUAUAAGGAGUGUAGACAAGCCUUCACUGUGUAUGAAAAAUUUACUCAACACCAGAGAAUUCAUAUUGAUGAGAAAUCCUGUGAACAUAAAAGAAUGUGUGAAGAACUUUCAUCGUGGCCUGGGAUUUGCUCAACAUCAGAGUAUUCAUACUGCUGAGAACUCCUUUGAGUGUAAAGAAUGUGGGAUAUUUUAUAGCCACACUAAAUGCCUUAGAGUUCAGAGAAGAUAAUUUUGGUGAGAAAGUUACUGAUGUGAGGAAUGUAGAGUAGCUGCCAUGUUCACAGUUUACUGCCCGUGAAAUAUUUUACUGGAUACAGGCGUACCUUGCUUAAUUGUGCAUUGCAGUUACUGCAUUUUAUACACACUGAAGGUUUGCAGCAACCUUGCAGUGAAUAAGUCUAUCAGCACCAUUUUCCAAACAGCAUAUGCACAUUUCAUGUCUUUGUGUCACACUUUGCUAGUUUUCAUAAUAUUUCAAACUUUUUCAUUGUUAAAUCUGUUAUGGUGAUCUGUGACCAGUGUUUUUUGAUUACUAGUGUAAUUGUUACUAGUGUAAUUGUUUGGGGAUACCACAAAUCCUGCCCAUAAAAGAUGGUGAACCUAGUUGAUAAUUGUUGUGGGUUUUGAAAGAAUAGUAAAAUAUAUACACAUAUCCCCCCCACCUAGAUUCAAAAUUGUUAACAAUUUGCCACAUUUAUUUUUUGUAUAUUUGUUGUACCAUUGAGAAUAAGUUUUAGACCAUUGAGAAUAAGUUUUAGAUAUCAUGACACUUUACUCCUUGUUACAUCAGCAUGUGUGUUACCCAAACAUAAAGACAAUAUCAUAUAACCAUAGUACCAUAAUUACCCUUAAGGAAAAUAUUCAUAAUUCUGUAAUAUCAUUCCAUCUUCAGAUUUCUUCCUUGGCCUGCAAACCAUCUUUUACAGCUAUUCAUUUUCUCUUUUUUUUUUUUUUUUUUUGAGAUGGAGUCUCGCUCUGUCGCCCAGACUGGAGUGCAGUGGUGCGAUCUGGGCUCACUGCAAGCUCUGCCUCCUGGGUUCACGCCAUUCUCCCGCCUCAGCCUCCUGAGUAGCUGGGACUAGAGGCACCCGCCACCAUGCCCAGCUAAUUUUUUGUAUUUUUAGUAGAGACAGGGUUUCACUCUGUUAGCCAGGAUGGUCUCGAUCUCCUGACCUCGUGAUCCACCCGCCUUGGCCUCCCAAAGUGCUGGGAUUACAGGCAUGAGCCAGCAUGCCUGGCCUACAGCUAUUCAUUUUCUAAGGAGAGUCCAUUGCAGAUUCUGCAUUGCAUUUGGUUAUCUCUCUUUAGUGUAUUGUAGCAUGGAAACCCCAUGAAAGUAUGCUCUCAAAUUAUGGUGGGUAUCAGAAUCCCCUGUGGAACUUAGUAAACCUACAGAAGUGUAGCCCUAGUUUAUAAGCCUGGGCCUCUGUUUUUUAUUAUUUCUCCAGGUUUUGUGUCUGUGAUACCAACCAGAGUUAGAGAGCCACUGGUCUAGAACAUUUCUCAUUUUAAAAAAAUGACAUUGAAUUUUGAGUAGCCCAGAAAUGUUGUUGGCUAUGUGUUUAGAUUUCUUUCUUUAUAGUGUCAUUUAGCCUUGUUCUUGGUUGUAUUUUCUUUACAAGGGAAAGUAAGUCCAGAGGCUUUCUUAGGUCUAGAUUAAACGUUUUGGGGAAGAAUACUUUGUAGGUUAUUUCUAUGUCAUAUUGUACUGUCAGAAAACAUUUAAGUACAGGUCCUUGCAUUAGUGAAACUAAGGAUGAUCAUUUGGGUAAGCUGGUAACCGCCGUAAGUCCAUUGUAAAGAUUUAGUUUGUAGUGGGUAAGUAAUCUAUGGAGAGACGUUGUCAUCUCUGAAAAGUUAUAGUCACGUGUACUUAAGCCCUGGAUUGAAUACAAAAUGAAAAUUGAAAUAGACUAUUGAGAAAUGAAUGCCAUUAAAGCGUCAACAUAAUUCAACUUGUGUGAUAUGGCUGACACUGUACUCAGUACAAAACUGGCACCCUUUGGAUUGUAUAGGGAGCCAAGAUUGUCCGGAACCUCUUUUUUGUUCAGCAUUUAUCACCAGCACCUAUACCAUGGCUGGUACAUGAGCUGUUGAUAAAAAUUUGAAAAAAUAUUAACCCUUUAAAUCAAGCUGUAAAACAUGAUACCAUUAAGCCGGGAGCAGUGGCCUCAUGCCUGUAAUCCCAGCACUUUGGGAGGCCAAGGUGGGCAGAUCACCUGAGGUCAGGAGUUUGAGACCAACUUGGCCAACAUGGCAAAACUCCAUCUCUCCUAAAAAUAAAAAAAUUAGCUGGACAUGGUGGUGCAUUCCUGUAAUCCCAGCUACUUGGGAGGCUGAGGCAGGAGAAUCACUCGAAAUUGGAAGGUGGAGGUGGCAGUGAGCCAAGAUCGUGCCACUGCACUCCAGCCUGGGCGACAAAGUGAGACUUCAUCUCAAAAAAACCCCAAAACAAAACAUGAUACCGAUGUGGCAUCAUGAAUUAGAUUAAAUUUUUUUUAAGAUUAAGAAUAAUCCUUUGUGAUUUUAUUCCAUUGUGUUGAAAAAUCUAUAAAGUGAUAAUUUAUAUUGAUAGCUUUCUUCUUUUUAUGAAUAUACCCUGGUCAGAUGAUUAUUCUUUCAAUAGACUACUUAAUUCUAUCUUUUACCAUUUAAUUGCAUCUAUAAUCAUAAGUAAAGUUAUAAUUUUCCAAGUAUUUUUCAGGUAUUGAUAUUGCAAUGAUGUUAUACAACUUAUAAAACAAGAUUAUAUAAAACUUGGCUUUCAAAUCUUAUGUUCCUAUUUUUUAUUUCCAGUUUCAUCUUUUUUCUAUCCAUUCUCUUGAACUUUCUUCUUUGAAAUCAGCAGAGUCCCUGGGUAUUAACCUAGCACAACUCCUUUCUGGGUCAUUGCACAUCCCGGUAGUAUCAUUAAGAGUUGUCAGAAAGAUCCCUGGCAGCCUUUCGGUGAAACUCUAUCAUCAUGCAAUCAUGGCAGUACUAUGUUGGAAGUCAGAGUCCCUUUGCAAACAUAAUAAAACACUUUAAUAUAUUUGUUAAAGUUACAAACCAAGUAUGUACAAAUUUAAAAAUCACGGCCAGGCACGGUGGCUCACGCCUGUAAUCCCCAACUUAAAAUGGUUUGACUUAUAAUUUUCAGCUUUAUAAUAGUACAAAAGUGAUAUGCUGCUAUAGUUUGGAUAUUUAUCCCCUCCAAAUCUCAUAUUGAAGUUUGAUCCCAAUGUUGGAGGUGGGGCCUAAUGGGAGGUGUGUGGGUCAUGGGAGAAGAUCCCUCAUGAAUAAAUUAAUGUCCUCUCUGGAUUGGGGGGUGAAUUAUCACUCUGUUAGUUCCUAUGAGAGCUGGUUGUACAAAAGAGCCUGGCACCUCCUUCCUCACCCUCUUGCUUCCUCUCUUGCCAUGUGAUGUCUGCAUACACUGCCCCCUUUCAUCUGCCAUGAGUGGAAGCAGCCUGAGGCCCUUACCAGAAGCAGAUGUUGCACCAUGAUUCUUGUAAAUCCUACAGAACACUGAGCCAAAUAAACCUCUUUCUUUAUUAAUAACCCAACCUCAGACAUUCCUUUAUAGCAACACAAAACUAAGACAUACUCAGUCAGAGUAUGCUCCUUGACUUAAAAUGGGGCUAUAUCUAGAUAAACCCAUUGUUAAAUUGAAAAUAUUGUAGACCAUAAAUGCACAUAUGGUGUAUGAUGUUUUCAAUUUAUGAUGGGUUUAUUUGGACAUAACUCCCCGUAAGUUGAGAAGCACCUGUAGUAAUUAUUAUUAUUUAUGCUCAAAUUGACAUAAUGUGGCCAGUAGGAAUCCAUUUACAUUUUUUUUUUACUACUUAUUUUUUUCUUUUGAUGUUUUAAAGGAAUAUUGUUUUCAGGCCGUAAGAGGAUGUUUAAGACUGACCCUGUUUGUUGGUUCAUGUCCCCCAUGCCUCUUGUCCUGAGUCAUGGAAUCAACUCAUGAUUUAAUACCCUCUUAUCUUAGGGAGUCCUGGUUCCUUUUAGAGGAAAAAAGAAUUAGAGACCAAAAAAUCUGGCUGCUGUGAGUGCACAUGGCAGUUACAGGUAUGGAAAAAAAGAUGCUGCUUUUGUUAGAAUUCUUUUAAUAGUUUCAGAGUUGAAAAUGUCAUCCUAAGGUCAGAAGUUCCCUCUGAAUUUUCUCAACUUACAUUUCUAUGAUCUGCUCUUGUUUGCAUUUGGUAUUUUAUUGAAUUAUGUUUUAUGUAUGGUGAUAGCUGAGAAGUUUAUCUCCUUUUAAGGCCUGGCUGAAAUGAUACAUUAAUCUGCCUCCCAUUUUUGGAGAUAUUGCUCUGAUUUAAAUUUGUCAUGGUGUUUCUGAGCAGCGUUGUAAAGAAACUUGUUUUAGAAUAUUCAGUCAUGGAUGUUAUCUUGAAUGUUCAUAGACUCCCCAGAAAAGAAGAAAAAGUAGACACAAGAUUUCUGUCAUCCUUUUACAGGGUAUUGUGAUCAUCCAGCUUGGGGUAUGAGGGAUAACGGACCUGUGUGUCUUAAUUUCCAGAAUACCAUUCCAUUUCAAUGAGUCUUCUGCACAAGUUGUGGUCUCAGGGAUUCACUGUCUUCAUUUGUAAUUGAUCAAAAUGAAACCAUCUCCAGGAUUCCUCAGUGGGUCAGGAUCUGUUAUUUAUUAGGCCCGCAUAUCCAUUCUACCCUGCUUUCAUGAUUAUAGAACCAGUAAUUUUUAUUGAUAGUUGGCUGUGACUAUCUAGAAUAAGGACUGCAGUUAUUUCUCCAAGGUGUUGUCAUGUGACAUAACUUAUGGCAAGUAGGAUGUAAGUGAAUAUUUUGGCAAUUCUGGAAACCUCUUAAAACAAACUAGCUUAAUAUAUUAAUAUUUGAGAAAUCUGGGUGAAGGGUAACCAGAAUUAUUUACUAUUCUUCCAAGUUCUGUAUAAGUCUGAGUGCUCAUUCCAUUCUGAUGCCAGAAUGGUAAAAUUCAUGAUUGGUUUAGAGCAAGGCCACAGUAUCAGGCUUACAUCCAUAUUAUAUGACAGAGAAAUUAACUUUUAUUAUAUUUUAUCCACUUUAAUUUGGGGCAGUUUUACUAUUUUACUCACAACCAAAUUUAAUCUUAAACGCUACAACUAGAUUGUCACAUGUAAAAAGUAAUAACCAUCAUUAUAUCUUUUAUGUUCUGUAAUUCCAAAGCACGGAUCUGUAGAGAACAGAGUGUCUAUCCCAUGCAUGUUGUCAUGUACUUAUCCCACACCCUAUUGAAAUCACAGUACCCAUAAGGGAGACAUUUUUUUUCUUCAAGAAUAUGUAUUUCUGCCACAUCUAUGAUUCUCCAGAAUGAGAUGACAGAAAAUGCUAAACUAUUGUUAAAUGACUAUAUGUAGUUCCACUUCUGGAUGGUAGAUGGGGGGGCUCUGCAAACUCAUUUUCUAAUAAAACUGGCAAAAAAAAAUGUA